GCCGCACCCACACCGCGCUGCGCAGUUUUGUUCUGCUCCAGCUGUUCGAAGGUGAUCCAGGGACAGGAGAUGCCCUGGAGGGGAAGGCGCUUCCGGCUCUGCAGACGCAAGAUGGCUGUCCUCUCUAAGGAAUAUGGUUUUGUGCUUCUAACUGGUGCUGCCAGCUUUAUAAUGGUGGCCCACCUAGCCAUCAAUGUUUCCAAGGCCCGCAAGAAGUACAAAGUGGAGUAUCCUAUCAUGUACAGCACGGACCCUGAAAAUGGGCACAUCUUCAACUGCAUUCAGCGAGCCCACCAGAACACGUUGGAAGUGUAUCCUCCCUUCUUAUUUUUUCUAGCUGUUGGAGGUGUUUACCACCCGCGUAUAGCUUCUGGCCUGGGCUUGGCCUGGAUUGUUGGACGAGUUCUUUAUGCUUAUGGCUAUUACACGGGAGAACCCAGCAAGCGUAGUCGAGGAGCCCUGGGGUCCAUCGCCCUCCUGGGCUUGGUGGGCACAACUGUGUGCUCUGCUUUCCAGCAUCUUGGUUGGGUUAAAAGUGGCUUGGGCAGUGGACCCAAAUGCUGCCAUUAAAGAAUUAUAGGGGUUUAAAAACUCUCAUUCAUUUUAAAUGACUUACCUUUAUUUCCAGUUACAUUUUUUUUCUAAAUAUAAUAAAAACUUACCUGGCAUCAGCCUCAUACCUAAAACUCCUGACUCUUACCACUCAUUUCCGUUUGAGUCUGUAUCUGAAAUCAGUAGCCUAGUCCUACUAGAUGAGAAAGGAGCCACAAGUAUUGUGCCCUCUCCUCACCCUUCCAGCAGAUGCUUCUGUAGUAUGUGAGGUUGAGAAAAAGUCUGAUUGUGGUGAUGUAGGUAUAGUCAUGCCACAGUGAUGAAAAAUUAAAGAAAAAUCUUCUAGCUCUCAGGAUAUGCAUUAUCACUUGCUACAGAUACUCCAAGGCCAAAGGAAUGCUUGAGCCUAAAAGUUCAAGACCAGCCUGGGCAACAUAGCAAAACCCCAUCUCUACAAAAAAAUAUACAACAGUUAGCCAGGCAUGAUGGCACAUGUCUGCAGUCCCAGCUACUUGGGAGGCUAAGGUGGGAGGAUCACUUGAGCCCAGGGUGUCAAGGCUGCAGUGAGUUAUGAUCACACUGCUGCACUCCAGCGUGGGUGACAGAGCAAGACCCUGUCUCAAAUAAAUAAAAAUUAAGUUUCUAUUAAA